GUCAUUCUGCAAAAGCUGCCCGAACAGGCUUUCCUCUGAAAAGCAGUGCCGUUCCUUUUUAGAAAGACUGAAUCUAAAUGUUGUCUCUGGAGACAAGAAGCCUUCAGUAUGUUAAAUUACUUUCAUUAUGUAUUUUCAGAUGCUUAUUGAUUCCACAGUAGGAAGAGUGAGAGACUGCAGCAGCCUCUAAGCAGCACUACAUGUUCCAUACAUUAGCAGUACUGCUGAAACAAUGGCACACUACAGACACAUAUUUUCAUUAAGGUCAUUUUCGAAGAGAUGUUUAUGACCCUCUUCCCCCAGUCCUCUACUAACAAGUGAACAAAAUGAAUCAAUCCAAACUGGAAAUGCUUCAACUACAUCAAGAAUUUAUCAAAUCUUUAGCAGAGGGCCAAUAGCAGCUAAUUCAGUAUUUACAACUGACAAUAUGAAGAAUGCAAUUGACUGAGCAUCUCCCUAGCUGUCUGAACUACGAACUGCAAGAUGUUCUUGUAACACGACUUUAAGACAUUAAGGAGUUAAAACCAGGGAAUAGGUCUACAUUACUGAUGGAAUAUAAAAAAUCAACUGUAUCCUAAGAAGAUGCUACAUAAAAUAACCACAAAAAGAAAAACAAUAUAACUGUAAAAGCCUGAAAAGAAUUUUUAAAAGGGGAAGUUUAUACUUUCAUAUACCAGAAUUGUGGAAGUUACUGAUUCUGGAAGACAUAAUGAAACAUGAAUUUCCAAAAAGAAAAGAAAAUACUUUAUCAGCACACAAAAGGAAGAUUUAGGAAGUGUUUUCUGCACUAAAUAUUCAGAUAUUCAUAUCAAUUGGUAUGACUAAUGGAUUUUUCUAUCUGACUUUUAUGACCAAUUAUGUAUCCUCUUCUAAUGAAAACAAACAAAAUUAAACAGCAGAUGGUUUUUAUCAAAAGGACAUGGCCUGGAUUUAUAAUAUAAAGCAAGUUAUGUGAUCAAGAAAUCAUUUCAAAAUAGUGAGCACUGCUAUUAAAAACAGAUUUACAAUGGUAACAAAAGGAUGUCUAAAUAUAUUUUAGAAGCUACAAACGUUAUGUUUCCUUUUUUGUUUUCACAUAUUCUGGAAAAUAAAGAAAUAUUAUCAUGUACUCCAUCAAAGGGAAACAUAAUUCCUAUCAUCUGAGGAAAUUCCUCUUGGCCGUGACUUUUUAAAGCAAAACAAAUACAAAUAUUAUGUACUGUUCUUUAGAAAUCCAUCAGCCAACUAAAUCUCAUAAUGCAUGCAGUUGAAGUAUUGGAGAGAAAACGAAAGAAUUCCUACAAGACAUGAAAUAAAACACAGCUACUUCACUGUUGUCAGGUAAAAAUUCAUGUCAAAAUCUGUCAAUGAUAUCAUGUAUCAAUUUGCCAAAAACUGUCAUAGUGAACCAAAAGGCCCAUAAGGCAACAGCAAACAGGUAGGUCAGAAGAUGCAUGCACCCCACCACACUGUUUAACAUUUACGAAAGAACAGAAUCUUGCUCUAGAGAAAAUGUAUUUUUCUUAAUCAUCAUUUAACUUGACAUUUCUGCUUUAUUUAAUUAUAAAUCUAACUGAUGUGACAAAGACCUGAUGUUUAAUCUGUCAGUUCAGAAAAUUUGGCACACUUAAAAUUUUCCAUUUUUAUAGGAUUUCAAUGUUAGCUAAGACCUUAACUUACUCGAAUAAAUAUACCUCUAGUAAUACUUCAUACUAAUUCAAAAGAAAUAAUGUUACCAUUUGUGUUUCUGCAAUAUUAUUCCCAAAAAAGUUCAUAAAUAAAACUGUAUUCUAAAACUUGUCAAAUAUAACAUUAAGUGAAAGUUAACAUGAAUUUUGAAAAUUAUUAGCUUUUAUAAUUUAUGUUGAAUAUGAUUUUGCAGUUGAAAUGCUGUAUUUGAAAUGUGAAAUAUAGUUGGUUGUAUGAGUUCAUAUUUUAAAAUGAAUAUACUGAUUAACUGACAUUUUAGCCCAGAACAUUAGACAUUAUUUUUUACAAAUUAUUCUAAACCCCUAUAUAUUAAAAUAUAGAUUUGCAUGAAUUAGCAAAAGCGUUUGUAUUUUUUUUUAAUUUUUCUUCAAAAUUAGACAAUGGGUGAUAUAUACAAAAGGCUUCACAGGUAAUGUGUAACUUUAAAAGCUUCCUCAAAAAACGGGCUUCACAUACUCCUUUUCCCUAAAAUUUCAUCUUUUACUUUAAAAACUCAGUUUAAACAAUGUCAACUGAUAUAUUCCUUUAAACUACUUCAAAAAUGGCUAUUUCUUAAUGUGAUAUUAAAUUUCAAUUUUCUGUUUCCACAAGAUACAAGAGGGUGUGGUCACAAAAUAAAUCAUUUCAUAGGAGUGAUUAAUGCUCUUUUACCAAGCUUUGUAGCUUUUUAUUUUAGCAUAAUGUCCCACUUCUUCUAAUUUUUAAGUUUGCCAACUGCAAAGUUCAGUGAGCAUUGUAACUGUGAUAUGUAAAAUAUUAAUCACUGGCCUAUUUCUGUGGGAAAUAACCCCAAAUAUCACCAAGCACAUUGUUGACUUCUGAAUAUGAAUUCAAUCAACAUGGAUAAAGCAUCUUAAACUAGUGCUCUGUACCAUUUGUCAUUUUAAAUGAACACUUGUCCUGUUCAUUUGAAAUCUCACAGGAAUAAUUACACCUACACUCAUUAUGCUAGAGCAUAUUAAAAUAGCAUUCAUUUGGUACCUACUCACAACAUUUAAAUGAAAUUUUAAGACACUGGGCUGAAAUUAAUUUUGUAUGCUAGGAAGUUUUAUCAUACAAAAAUACACUUUAUCUCAAAUAAUAAGCUUGAAAUACUCAAAUGAGAAAAGCCCUUUAGCAUAUUAACUUUGCACUACAGAGGAACAAUUUCCAUAGUUAUUUCUUCAAAAGGAAAACACAAUUUUCUUUUAUAUCAAAACAAUGCAAACUUGAUGGUUCUUAAUUCUACAUUUUCUAUUAAUAGUUUACAAACUUAAAAAUUAAACUAAGUACACAAUUGAAAGAUUUUUUUUCUUACAAAGAACACGUUAUACGUCAUUUAAAUUGCCAAAUAUCAAAUAGUUUAUUCUAUUUCACUUUCUAGGGAAAAAAACCAACUGCUCCAAAAGAAUGUGUUUUUCUCCCAUUCUGGAAAUCAACAUGCAGUCUGAAUCUAACAUUACAGUGCGAGAUGACAUUGAUGACAUCAACACCAAUAUGUACCAACCACUAUCAUAUCCGUUAAGCUUUCAAGUGUCUCUCACCGGAUUUCUUAUGUUAGAAAUUGUGUUGGGACUUGGCAGCAACCUCACUGUAUUGGUACUUUACUGCAUGAAAUCCAACUUAAUCAACUCUGUCAGUAACAUUAUUACAAUGAAUCUUCAUGUACUUGAUGUAAUAAUUUGUGUGGGAUGUAUUCCUCUAACUAUAGUUAUCCUUCUGCUUUCACUGGAGAGUAACACUGCUCUCAUUUGCUGUUUCCAUGAGGCUUGUGUAUCUUUUGCAAGUGUCUCAACAGCAAUCAACGUUUUUGCUAUCACUUUGGACAGAUAUGACAUCUCUGUAAAACCUGCAAACCGAAUUCUGACAAUGGGCAGAGCUGUAAUGUUAAUGAUAUCCAUUUGGAUUUUUUCUUUUUUCUCUUUCCUGAUUCCUUUUAUUGAGGUAAAUUUUUUCAGUCUUCAAAGUGGAAAUACCUGGGAAAACAAGACACUUUUAUGUGUCAGUACAAAUGAAUACUACACUGAACUGGGAAUGUAUUAUCACCUGUUAGUACAGAUCCCAAUAUUCUUUUUCACUGUUGUAGUAAUGUUAAUCACAUACACCAAAAUACUUCAGGCUCUUAAUAUUCGAAUAGGCACAAGAUUUUCAACAGGGCAGAAGAAGAAAGCAAGAAAGAAAAAGACAAUUUCUCUAACCACACAACAUGAGGCUACAGACAUGUCACAAAGCAGUGGUGGGAGAAAUGUAGUCUUUGGUGUAAGAACUUCAGUUUCUGUAAUAAUUGCCCUCCGGCGAGCUGUGAAACGACACCGUGAACGACGAGAAAGACAAAAGAGAGUCUUCAGGAUGUCUUUAUUGAUUAUUUCUACAUUUCUUCUCUGCUGGACACCAAUUUCUGUUUUAAAUACCACCAUUUUAUGUUUAGGCCCAAGUGACCUUUUAGUAAAAUUAAGAUUGUGUUUUUUAGUCAUGGCUUAUGGAACAACUAUAUUUCACCCUCUAUUAUAUGCAUUCACUAGACAAAAAUUUCAAAAGGUCUUGAAAAGUAAAAUGAAAAAGCGAGUUGUUUCUAUAGUAGAAGCUGAUCCCCUGCCUAAUAAUGCUGUAAUACACAACUCUUGGAUAGAUCCUAAAAGAAACAAAAAAAUUACCUUUGAAGAUAGUGAAAUAAGAGAAAAAUGUUUAGUGCCUCAGGUUGUCACAGACUAGAGAAAAGUCUCAGUUUCACCAAAUCCACAUUCAAAUGAGUUUUAAAUUUAAAUUGUAAAAACUGAUAUUACUGCCAAAUAUAAGAAAAAUAUUUUAAGUAUUGGUUAUGUUGUAAAUUUUCAAUGUGAAUGUCAAUUAGAUAGGUCAUAUAUAUUCAAUUUCUUCAUUACUUAAUGUAUUUGUUGCAUGGCAGUUUGUUAAAGUACUAUCAUGUGUAUAUUUUGUCAAUAUUAUGUCCAACAGAAAAUAUUCAUGUAAGUCAUAUUUUUUAAGGAAUAAAUACAUAGCCUUAAAACAGUGUAUAACUUUAAAAUGUAACUGACAUAGGUAUCCUUGCUUUAUUUUUUAAGUUAAAAUGCAUUGUUUCUAAGCCACAAACUACAGAUAUAUUUAGAUUACAACUGGAGUAGCAUUUUAAUCUAAAAACCAAAAUUAUGGGCUCAAAACAAUCCAGUAUUUUCCAUACCACUAUGCUAUGUUUCCUGGUAUAGUGUAUUUGCUAUAUUUGAUGCAUCACAAAUAAUUAAGUACGUAUGAAGCUUUAUUCUUUUAAAUGUAAAAAAUCAUAGAAUUUAUCAAAAUUUUAAAAUUAAUGAACCAAAAAAACCUCUGUAUACACACCAAAAUAGAGAAACUUUAAAAUUCAUGCUUACUAGGAAAAAAAAGAUUGAUUUUCUAAGUUCAAGGACAGUAUGCCUAUAAUAUACAAAUGAAAUGAAACUAAAGGGAAGGAAGAAUACUAAAACACCAGCCUCUUUCUUCCUUCCUCACUUUGCUUAAGUCUAAGCCAAAUGCUCUGGAUUAAUAUAGUGCAAUGAUUUUAAAAAAAAAAAAAAAAAAAAAAAGAACAGUACAUCAAAAUAAGCUGACUUCCUAACUUUAUUCAACUCAGCUCUUUUGUAUAAUAGAAAGUUAACUACCCAAAUCUGAAUACCAGGAAUGAAAAAAAAAAGACUUUAAAUCAUUAUAGAAAAGUCUAACAAAGCCUCUAAUAUUAGAUACAUACAACUUUAGGGUAAUACACUUUAUACAAUGUUCCCACCAAAUCAUAGCUCCCAAGUAAUUCAAAAUGAGUUGUUUUAUUUCCACACUGAAAUCACUAAGGUAACAAUAAGUCUUGUCACUUUUCUACCGUACCAUCACUUAAUUUAACUUUAGGCAUUUUUCUCUCCCACCCUCAAUUCAUGUGGGAAAAUCAUGAAAUUACUAACCCUAACUACAGAUUACAAGAAUUGGGAACCUCAUAUCAAACAAAUAUUUUCCAAUUGUUAUAAUGUAAUAAUCUAUCGAUAAGUGUCAAUAUCACUAUCAGAAAUUUAGCAAUAAGUUAUUUAAAAUAGGAAAAUACUGCAUUGUAAUUGGUCAGCUGAACAACUUUUAUUCUAUUUUCUGAAACUGUAUCCACUAAACCAAGUAGCAAUUCAUUUUUAAAGAAAAUAUUAAAUGUCUAAAAAUUCAAUAAUAUAUCACUUUUAUAUAAAUAAAUGAGAUUUAUCCAGUCUAGUUUACUGAAUACCCUAAUCCUUGGAGAAAUGAAUACCAUGCAGUAGCUUGAACUCACUAAGGUUACAUGACAAAUUAAAUAGUAAUUUACUUCUGAUAAUAAUGUUAACAUAAUGUCAAAUCUUGGCAAAAGCCCAAUUUCCUUCUGUCUUAUUUUCUACUGUUUUUUGGAAUUUAAAAAAAUGCUUCAAUUUGACAAAAUGUAGCAUAAGCAAGUAAGAUAUUUUUUGAAACCCCAAAGAGAAAUUAACACUUCAGGCACAAAAGGAUUAAGAAAAUUUUCGUUUAGUAAAUACAUUUGGCACAGACCAGCUCCUAAUCUUCUUUUAUUUUUUACCCCAGGAAAUAAAACAAGCUCAUUAAUAUCUUCAUUUAAGAAUUUAAAAAAUGAAUUUUAUAAUUGGACUCCCAAGCAUAAAUUAAAAUUUUAAUAUCUAGUUUUAUAAUCUCAAUAAAAAUUAGACUAUUUUUAGAACCUUCAUAUUAAGAAAAACUCCCUUGUGUUUUAAAUAUUUUUACUCUUCAGGUUUAUAACUAUGCCAAAGAACUCAGUAUAAAAAAGAGAUUUCUAAUAUAUUUGUCUAAACUGCUUUCAUGCCUUCUUGUCCUCUGUAAUAAGAAAUUAAAUAAGAAAUAAAUGGUAAAUAUUAUAUUGCCCUUUAAACUGCUAUCAUUUCUAUACUUGACACUGAAGCAGACAUUUAACAAGCAUUGUUGACCAUCCGUAAUGAUCUUUCAGGUAUACAAAAGUGCAUCAACUGAUUUACGACAAAGAAAACUCAUACCUAUCAGAAAACUUCUAACAGCUUUUUAAUGUGCUAAGUAGUAUAUAAUAUGUAAACCAAAAUAAUAUGUGUUAAAAAUUUAGCUUCAAGAACAAGUCACAACUAUGUUUCCAACUACUGACCUCAGCUUAAAUGUGAGAAUGAGAAGCUUAGACAACUUUUUGUAUUAAACAUCUGUUCUAUGAAAAGACGAAA